CUCUCUCUCGGCUGCCGCUGCUGCCGUUGGCUCUUAUUCUCCUCCUCCUCCUCCUCUCUCCUCCUCUCUGCUUCUCUCUGCUCCUCUCUCCUCCUCUCUCCUCCUCCUCCUCCUCCACCUCCUCCUCCUUCUCCCCCUCUUUCUCCCCCUCUUUCUCUCUUCUUUCUCCCCCGUCCCCCCGCCCCCUCCCCCCAGGCCUGAUGAGCAGGUCUCGAGCCUCCAUCCAUCGGGGGAGCAUCCCCGCGAUGUCCUAUGCCCCCUUCAGAGAUGUACGGGGACCCUCUAUGCACCGAACCCAAUACGUUCAUUCCCCGUAUGAUCGUCCUGGUUGGAACCCUCGGUUCUGCAUCAUCUCGGGGAACCAGCUGCUCAUGCUGGAUGAGGAUGAGAUACACCCCCUACUGAUCCGGGACCGGAGGAGCGAGUCCAGUCGCAACAAACUGCUGAGACGCACAGUCUCCGUGCCGGUGGAGGGGCGGCCCCACGGCGAGCAUGAAUACCACUUGGGUCGCUCGAGGAGGAAGAGUGUCCCAGGGGGGAAGCAGUACAGCAUGGAGGGUGCCCCUGCUGCGCCCUUCCGGCCCUCGCAAGGCUUCCUGAGCCGACGGCUAAAAAGCUCCAUCAAACGAACGAAGUCACAACCCAAACUUGACCGGACCAGCAGCUUUCGCCAGAUCCUGCCUCGCUUCCGAAGUGCUGACCAUGACCGGGCCCGGCUGAUGCAAAGCUUUAAGGAGUCACACUCUCAUGAGUCCUUGCUGAGUCCUAGCAGUGCAGCUGAGGCAUUGGAGCUCAACUUGGAUGAAGAUUCCAUUAUCAAGCCAGUGCACAGCUCCAUCCUGGGCCAGGAGUUCUGUUUUGAGGUAACAACUUCAUCAGGAACAAAAUGCUUUGCCUGUCGGUCUGCGGCCGAAAGAGACAAAUGGAUUGAGAAUCUGCAGCGGGCAGUAAAGCCCAACAAGGACAACAGCCGCCGGGUAGACAAUGUGCUAAAGCUGUGGAUCAUAGAGGCCCGGGAGCUGCCCCCCAAGAAGCGGUACUACUGUGAGCUCUGCCUGGAUGACAUGCUGUAUGCACGCACCACCUCCAAGCCCCGCUCUGCCUCUGGGGACACCGUCUUCUGGGGCGAGCACUUCGAGUUUAACAACCUGCCGGCUGUCCGUGCCCUGCGGCUGCAUCUGUACCGUGACUCAGACAAAAAGCGCAAGAAGGACAAGGCAGGCUAUGUCGGCCUGGUGACUGUGCCAGUGGCCACCCUGGCUGGGCGCCACUUCACAGAGCAGUGGUACCCUGUAACCCUGCCAACAGGCAGUGGGGGAUCUGGGGGCAUGGGUUCGGGAGGGGGAGGGGGCUCGGGGGGUGGCUCAGGGGGCAAGGGCAAAGGAGGUUGCCCGGCUGUGCGGCUGAAAGCACGUUACCAGACAAUGAGCAUCUUGCCCAUGGAGCUAUAUAAAGAGUUUGCAGAGUAUGUCACCAACCAUUAUCGGAUGCUGUGUGCAGUCUUGGAGCCCGCCCUGAAUGUCAAAGGCAAGGAGGAGGUUGCCAGUGCACUAGUUCACAUCCUGCAGAGUACAGGCAAGGCCAAGGACUUCCUUUCAGACAUGGCCAUGUCUGAGGUAGACCGGUUCAUGGAACGGGAGCACCUCAUAUUCCGCGAGAACACGCUUGCCACUAAAGCCAUAGAAGAGUAUAUGAGACUGAUUGGUCAGAAAUACCUCAAGGAUGCCAUUGGAGAAUUCAUCCGUGCUCUGUAUGAAUCUGAGGAAAACUGCGAGGUAGACCCUAUCAAGUGCACAGCAUCCAGUUUGGCAGAGCACCAGGCCAACCUGCGAAUGUGCUGUGAGUUGGCCCUGUGCAAGGUGGUCAACUCCCACUGCGUGUUCCCGAGGGAGCUGAAGGAGGUGUUUGCUUCAUGGCGGCUGCGCUGCGCAGAGCGAGGCCGGGAGGACAUCGCAGACAGGCUUAUCAGCGCCUCACUCUUCCUGCGCUUCCUCUGCCCAGCGAUUAUGUCGCCCAGUCUCUUUGGGCUUAUGCAGGAGUACCCAGAUGAGCAGACCUCACGAACCCUCACCCUCAUUGCCAAGGUCAUCCAGAACCUGGCCAACUUUUCCAAGUUUACCUCAAAGGAGGACUUUCUGGGCUUCAUGAAUGAGUUUCUGGAGCUGGAAUGGGGUUCCAUGCAGCAGUUUUUGUAUGAGAUCUCCAAUCUGGACACGCUAACCAACAGCAGUAGCUUUGAGGGUUACAUCGACUUGGGCCGAGAGCUCUCCACACUGCAUGCCCUACUCUGGGAGGUGCUGCCCCAGCUCAGCAAGGAAGCCCUCCUGAAGCUGGGUCCACUGCCCCGGCUCCUCAACGACAUCAGCACAGCUCUGAGGAACCCCAACAUCCAAAGGCAGCCAAGCCGCCAGAGUGAGCGGCCCCGGCCUCAGCCUGUGGUACUGCGGGGGCCAUCGGCUGAGAUGCAGGGCUACAUGAUGCGGGACCUCAACAGCUCCAUCGACCUUCAGUCCUUCAUGGCUCGAGGCCUCAACAGCUCUAUGGACAUGGCUCGCCUCCCCUCCCCAACCAAGGAAAAGCCACCCCCACCACCGCCUGGUGGUGGUAAAGACCUGUUCUAUGUAAGCCGUCCACCCCUGGCCCGUUCCUCACCAGCAUACUGCACGAGCAGCUCGGACAUCACAGAGCCAGAGCAGAAGAUGCUGAGUGUCAACAAGAGUGUGUCCAUGCUGGACUUACAGGGUGAUGGGCCUGGUGGCCGCCUCAACAGCAGCAGUGUUUCGAACCUGGCGGCCGUAGGGGACCUGCUGCACUCAAGCCAGGCCUCGCUGACAGCAGCCUUGGGGCUACGGCCUGCGCCUGCCGGACGCCUCUCCCAGGGGAGUGGCUCAUCCAUCACGGCGGCUGGCAUGCGCCUCAGCCAGAUGGGUGUCACCACAGACGGUGUCCCUGCCCAGCAACUGCGAAUCCCCCUCUCCUUCCAGAACCCUCUCUUCCACAUGGCUGCUGAUGGGCCAGGUCCCCCAGGCGGCCAUGGAGGGGGCGGUGGCCAUGGCCCACCUUCCUCCCAUCACCACCACCACCACCAUCACCACCACCGAGGUGGAGAGCCCCCUGGGGACACCUUUGCCCCAUUCCAUGGCUAUAGCAAGAGUGAGGACCUCUCUUCCGGGGUCCCCAAGCCCCCUGCUGCCUCCAUCCUUCAUAGCCACAGCUACAGUGAUGAGUUUGGACCCUCUGGCACUGACUUCACCCGUCGGCAGCUUUCACUCCAGGACAACCUGCAGCACAUGCUGUCCCCUCCCCAGAUCACCAUUGGUCCCCAGAGGCCAGCCCCCUCAGGGCCUGGAGGUGGGAGCGGUGGGGGCAGCGGUGGGGGUGGCGGGGGCCAGCCGCCUCCAUUGCAGAGGGGCAAGUCUCAGCAGUUGACAGUCAGCGCAGCCCAGAAACCCCGGCCAUCCAGCGGGAAUCUAUUGCAGUCCCCAGAGCCAAGUUAUGGCCCCGCCCGUCCACGGCAACAGAGCCUCAGCAAGGAGGGCAGCAUUGGGGGCAGCGGGGGCAGCGGUGGCGGAGGGGGUGGGGGGCUGAAGCCCUCCAUCACCAAGCAGCAUUCUCAGACACCAUCCACAUUGAACCCCACAAUGCCAGCCUCUGAGCGGACAGUGGCCUGGGUCUCCAACAUGCCUCACCUGUCGGCUGACAUCGAGAGUGCCCACAUCGAGCGGGAAGAGUACAAGCUCAAGGAGUACUCAAAAUCGAUGGAUGAGAGCCGGCUGGAUAGGGUGAAGGAGUACGAGGAGGAGAUUCACUCACUGAAAGAGCGGCUGCACAUGUCCAACCGGAAGCUGGAAGAGUAUGAGCGGAGGCUGCUGUCCCAGGAAGAACAAACCAGCAAAAUCCUGAUGCAGUAUCAGGCCCGACUGGAGCAGAGUGAGAAGAGGCUAAGGCAGCAGCAGGCAGAGAAGGAUUCCCAGAUCAAGAGCAUCAUUGGCAGGCUGAUGCUGGUGGAGGAGGAGCUGCGCCGGGACCACCCCGCCAUGGCUGAGCCGCUGCCAGAACCCAAGAAGAGGCUGCUCGACGCUCAGGAGAGGCAGCUUCCCCCCUUGGGUCCAACAAACCCGCGUGUGACGCUGGCCCCACCGUGGAAUGGCCUGGCCCCCCCAGCCCCACCACCCCCACCCCGGCUGCAGAUUACGGAGAACGGCGAGUUCCGAAACACCGCAGACCACUAGCCCACCCAGCAUCAGAGACCUUCUCUUCCUUUCCUGUGCACCCCACCCUGUAACAGCACCAACCACCAGGAUUGGACAUCACCGAGGAACAGCGGGAUUGCCUCCCCGAAUGCCUCCCUGGGAGGCACACUGAUUGCCCACCCCCACCACUGCACCAUUUCCAGGAGGGAGAGUGGGGACCCUCAGCCGCCCCCUUUUCCUUCCCAUUGGGGUGCUGCCCUCUCUUUGACCCCCAGGGACCCUUGCCCCAGGACACCGCCUACCCCGUACAGACCCCUUCACUCCGGGGUGCUAUCCCCAUCCUCUGCCUCAUCGUUCCCCUGAGCACUGGGGGACAGACCCUCACCCCCACCCUGGGGGUGUGGCACCUCCAAACUUUCAACUUCAGGGUGAUUUUUUUAGCAGUAACCAGAGCUGACAAUCUAACUCCCCUCCACCGCCCCAUUUUGGCCUCCCCUGCCCCCCUUGUUAUGGGGAGGGGACCCCGGGUGAGGGGGCCCUAUUACCCCUUGAUUUCUCAGGAGCGUCUGGGGGGGCUCAGCACGCACAAACUCCUUCUCCUUCUACCACUCUUAAAUUUACUCCCUCCCCACCCAGAACCCAGAUGGGGUGGAGGGGGCCACCGGGGCAGGGAGGGGGCGGCAAGGGGGGAAUGGGAGUUGUCUCCCCUUCUCCCCACACCUGAUCUGCUCUCGGCUGGUCCCAGAGCGGGGUGAGGGGGCUUAUGCCCCCCCCUCCCCCAGUGUGUUGGGUGGGGUGGAAUUGAGGUUAGGGUGAGGGGUCAGGGUUUAGGAGGGUGUGUAUGUUGGGAGGACAGGCUAGUUGAUCUGUCCUACUCUGACACACAGUCCCCUCUGCCCCUUCCUUCUCUCUUCUUGGUCUCUACUCCCAGGGGGAGGGGGGAACUUACUCUAGGAAAAGCCAUGUCUCUCUCCCCCAGGGUGGGGGGACCUGUGUUGGAGGAGGGGUGUUGGGGGGCCCCCUUCCAUGACUCUGUCCCCUGGGGGAGGUAGGACAGGGCUGGGCUUCCCUCUCAUCCUCCCCCUCCCAAUCUCCUUCCACCUCCCUCCCUCCCGCCAGCUCCACGAUUUUUCGGUGUUUCUCUGUACAUAGUUUUCUGGCGGGAUAGGGGAGGUAGGAUGGAUGGGGUUUGGGGUGGGUAGGCCAUGGGAGGGGAGAAGCCCCUCCUUGGCACCCCCUCUUCCCUGACUGCUGUCCCCUACCCAGCCUUGCCCCCUUCAUCCUUUUGCGUUUGGUAUUGAGACUCUCCUAGACUCUACUCCUCUUUCUUUUGUAUGGACAGUUCCCCUUCAGUCCCAUCCCCCUACACAUACACCCAGCCGGGGCCAAAUUUAUACUUAUAUAAAAGUUGUAAAUAUGUGAAAUUUUAUCCCUGUGCCCUUUCCCCACCUCAGGCCCUACCCCUGGACCCUCCCCAACCUUCCUUCUCUCUUCUUUGGCUGUUGUAAUUAUCUGGGGUUUGUACUGUACAUAUCCGGGGUGUGUGUGUGUGGGCUGGGGGCAACCCUUCUGUACAGAGCUUCCUGGCCCCCUCCCCCCCCGCCCCUCUGCUUCCCUCCCCACCCACCACCUCAAGGGUAGGGAGUUGCUCUUCCUACCUGUUUUAUUUUGUUUUCUCGUUCUCCCUCCCCACCCCACUCCCAGCCUUAUCUAUCCCCCCUCACUGUCCCCUUUUCUCCACUCCCAGCCCCAUUUCCUUUUUUUCUGGAGUGUGUGGUGAAACAGAAAAAAACAUGUUUAAUAAACGGAGAUUGUUCUUUUA